AUUCAGUCAGGAAAACCAGUCAGGAGGAGACUGCUAGGCAUUAAAUUGAGCACAGAUGAGAGCCCAAACAAGGGUGGUAGCACUGGAAACUGGGAAGAAGUGACAGACUUGAAUGACAUUCAAGUUAGAAUUGGCAAGUCCUGGUGAUCAUUUAGAAGUAGGGAGUGAAAAAGAGUCCCUGGAAGAGACCCCAAAGUCUCCACUGUGGGUGGCUGGAAGAUACGGAUGCUGUUAAUAUAAAGGAGGAAAACAGGAGGAAGGGCAAGAAAGUUUUGGUGAGAAGGAUGAAGUCUGCAUGUUGAAUUAGUAGUGAUAGCAAGACAUGCAUGUAGUAACUCCAACCAGAAGCUGGAAUUGUGAAUCUGGAGCUGGGGAUAUUUGCGCUAGAGACCUAGUGAGGAAACAGUUUACAAACAUGAAGCCAGGGGUGUGGGUGAGAGUGACUGUGGAGUGGACCCUUCAAGAUAGCCUUAAUAUAAAGUGUGGAUAGAAGUUGUGAUUUCCCGCAAGAAGCUGGAGGCUGGGACUCACAGGGCAAGUGGGCUGGGACACACAGUGCUGAGGUGCAGUAUAAGGGUGGUCAGGAGCACCAAAUGCAGAGUGCAAGCAAACAUUGUUCAUAUGCAUAACCUAUUAAUAUUUGUAAACUACAGUAAUGCUUUUAAAAUCUUAGGAUGUUUCAAGGUACUAAGACGCACUUCACUAAAUAAUAGGUCCUAUAGUAGCUGAAAAUAGAUUGUAGCUUUCCAAAGUGCCUUGAAUUGCAGGAUGCAUUUUACAUACUAAGAGAAGAAUCAUAUACCAUAAAUGUUUUCUUUUACAAGACAGUGGCUACCUGGGAGCAUCAUGUAGAGAUGUCAUCUGAGCAAUGAAUGUCCAGGCUCAGUGGGAAAGAGCACUGGGAUCUGUAGCAAUAUCUGCCCUGUGUGGAAGGGCGGGGACCACUGUGCCUAAAUUGGCUUUCCCUCAAUUAAAGGCUUUCCAAGCCAUGGCUGAAUUCCUUAGUGAUAUAGGAAAGGACCUUCACAAUUUGGGCUCAAGAGAUAGAACAAUGGAUAAUGACCCUGCCAUUACUAUUUUCUGUGCACAGUUAAUAUCUCUUUUUCCGUAUGGUUGGUCUCACCAUUUUCUUUCUGAUAAGAGGCGCUUGCACCAAUUCCAGGCUUCCUUCAGGAUUUUAAUCAUCCUUACAGCCUCUUUGAGAAUGAUUGAACUUCCAAAUUCCCUGAAGUUAAAAUUUUAAAUUCUAUUAAACAUUUUUUCGAGUAUUUCAUUACUUUUA